CCCAGUUUCUCCGUCAGCCUGCGGGUCCCGGCUGGCGGCUGCUUCCGGUAGGAGAGCGGUGUAGAGCGAGCAGGUCUCAGCUCCUCGUCAUGUCAUACGGUCCCUUAGACAUGUACCGGAACCCGGGGCCCUCGGGGCCCCAGCUCCGGGACUUCAGCAGCAUCAUCCAGACGUGCAGCGGCAACAUCCAGCGGAUCAGCCAAGCCACUGCUCAGAUAAAGAAUUUGAUGAGCCAGCUAGGAACUAAGCAGGACUCAAGCAAGCUACAGGAAAAUCUGCAACAGUUACAACACUCCACAAAUCAGCUCGCCAAGGAAACAAAUGAAUUGCUGAAAGAAUUAGGGUCCUUGCCCCUUCCCUUAUCUACUUCAGAACAGCGCCAGCAGAGACUUCAGAAGGAACGCCUCAUGAAUGACUUCUCUGCAGCCUUAAACAAUUUCCAGGCUGUGCAGAGAAGGGUAUCUGAAAAGGAAAAGGAGAGUAUUGCCAGAGCAAGAGCUGGAUCUCGUCUUUCUGCAGAAGAGAGGCAAAGAGAGGAGCAGCUGGUCUCAUUUGACAGCCAUGAGGAGUGGAACCAGAUGCAGAGCCAGGAGGAUGAGGUGGCCAUCACUGAGCAGGAUUUGGAACUUAUUAAAGAAAGAGAAACGGCAAUUCGGCAGCUGGAGGCUGACAUUUUGGAUGUCAAUCAGAUAUUUAAAGAUUUGGCCAUGAUGAUCCAUGACCAGGGUGAUCUGAUUGAUAGCAUAGAAGCCAAUGUGGAAAGCUCAGAGGUGCACGUCGAAAGAGCCACUGAACAGUUACAGCGAGCUGCUUACUAUCAGAAAAAAUCUCGCAAGAAGAUGUGUAUCCUGGUGCUUGUCCUGUCAGUGAUUAUUCUAAUCUUGGGACUUAUUAUCUGGCUAGUUUAUAAAACGAAGUGAUUGCCUCCGAUCGUUCUCCCGCUGAGCUGUUUUCAAGGGCAAGUGCUUGUUGAAGUCUUGCCAGAACAAACUGAUCACAAGAAGACAGCAUAUAUCAGAACGUCCUGUAAUCAUUUAGUUAGAAACUAACUACUAACUAGUCUUUGGAAUUCGUGACCUAUGGAGACAGUAAUUAUCAAUUUAUUGAUUCUAUUGAUUUCUCAAAUUAGGAAUUAACUUAUGUGGAUUUUGCUUCCUCUUGUAUUCUGAUUGCCCUUCAUCCCAAGUGUUUACUGAAAAUUCCAUUCUAGAUAUUCUUGUUUUGACAAAUGACACUACAGUCUCGUAAUAUUGUCUUUUAUGUAUAUACAAAAUUUACCUUUUUACUAGCAUCUGAGAUAGAGUUACUUUCUGGUACCCAGUAUAUUGGAGUCUGUCAGAAACUCUAUAAUAGGCCACCAGUUUUUAUUAUUUAACAUUUUUAUUUGAAUUUCUAAGAAGCCUAUUCUCUAUCUAUUUUGAAAGAUUUUGGCACUAUAUUUAAUUGGAAGGUAAAAUAUUGUACAUGUGAUCCAGAGUAAAUGAGAAGUCUCUAUCUGAGCUGGUCAGUUACUGGAGUACAUGUUACUAAUCUGGGUUUAAAGUUUACUUCAUUAUCUGCUAGUGUCAUCCACAGCAGUUCAUCCUCAUCCACACUAAGCCAUCCUGUUAGCUUUUAAAGGAAGUUAAUUUAAUUAACAUUAAUAUACUCUAUGGGCUCCCUCUCCCACCUGUCUGCAUAGAAAGGCAGAAUUAGACAUAGCAUGCUUUGGAAAAGCAAAUAGGAAUUGUUGGGAAUGAUUUAAUCUUGUUGUUGUUGUUGUUGUUGUUCACUUGUGGUUCUACAUUCCUGGUGAAUGAUGAAUGUUGCUGUCAAAGGGCUGCCCCCUACCUUAUAAGGGUUGCUGGGCAUUUGAAGGCAGGAAGAUUUUUAAAGAUAGAUUGAGGUUGGUUUAAAAUUAUUCCUGUAAACCAACAAUAAAGCAAAGAAGAGGUUCAUUUUUGUAAAUAACACUGGUUUCAAAUAGUGAUGUUAGACUUAACCUAAUUUAUAAACAAGAGAUUAAUAUCUCCAUGCAUAGUUUUAGACAAAAAAAGAUGUUUCAAUAAAAUUACUGUCUUGUAAUAUAAAUGUUGUCCACUUCCCUUUUCCACAGGCCUAGAACAGUUAAAGGGAACAUAAUUUGUUUAGGCUCCCACAUAAAUGUGAAUCUGGCCAACAACUUUGGUUCAUCCUUUAGUGAAUUAGAGGAUUUGGCUACCCUGAGUAUAUUUAUAUUCAUUUCUUCUGUUCUCCUUCUGUUAUUAUACUUAAUCUUCUAAACUAAACUAAUGUGAACAGUAGGGAAGCAAGGGCCCAAAUGCAUAAGUUUCUUUGCACUGUUGCACUUACUUAAUACAAAUAAAUGUUUUUUAAAGCUUUUGUAGUAUGUUUUUAUGAGUUAACAUCCUAAUGUGGUAGGUAUUAGGUAAUGUGCUGUCAUGAGAAAAAUUGAGACUUCCAAGAAAACUGGACACCAGGUGAGGGUUGGUUUGGAGACGGAAUAGGUGUAGCUGCCUUUCCUUGAAAAACAGUGUGUAGAGAUGGCUGAGUGCAAUGGCUCACACUUGUAAUCCCAACACUUUGGAAGGCUGAGGCGGGAGGAUCAGUAUAUCGGUACGUCUGAGCCCAAGAGUUCAAGAUCAGCCUGGGCAGUAUAGCAAGACCCCAUCUCCAUUUUUUUUUUAAUGAUUUUUUAAUUAAAAAAAAGAACAACAGGAUAGAGCUGUUGGGGUGGCACAGUGGCCCAAAGAGCAGCUUCAGAGAUAAUUCCUUGGUUCUAUGAUCCCUGUUUAACUCCAAAUUACAGUCGGACUUGGAUACAUCAUUUGUAACAUUGUAGGAAAGAAAAAAGUCUUGGUUGUGAAAAACGAUUUGCAUUUGGGUAAAAUAAAGUGACCAUGCUUUUGUUCUGUAAUACUGUGUGACCUGUGGUUGUUGUAAUGGUGAUCAUGGAGAGCAAAUAUGAACUUGGCCUGGAUUUUAAAUGGCCUAGAAUUUGUGGUAGUUGCCAAAGAGGUUCUCCUAGGUGGUCUUAAUAAACCUAUUCACAGAA